CCAGCCUCGCCCUCCCCUUUCUCGGAGGAGAAACUGAGGCCCGGCAAGCUUUGGGCCCAGGGAGCUUGCGAGGAAGGAGUGGGCUGAGUUUGGGGCUGAGGACUGUCCCCCGCGGUAUUUCUGAAUUCCACCCAGUAGCCUGAGCCUCCCAGGCACACCCAUACCUGUCUCCCUAACCAAAAUAGAGUUGGCACAUAAUACCUGUUUGUAGACUCAACAGAGGUCAAAGGCAAGCGGGAACUACCUACCAAAGACGCCUUUAUCCCAUCUGACCUUCCGAACUUGUCCUGCCUGCUUCCAUCCUUCUCUCCAGCGCCUUCUUCCCCCGGUGUCCUGUGGCAAUAACUGCUCUUGACCGCUCUCUGCCAUCCUCCUACCCACCCCAGCUCUCAGGGCAGGGCUGAGCAUCCUGGGAGGCUGUGGCACUUUGCUCAGAUCUGCAGGGAAUCAUGUUCUCUCUUCCCACGGUGGCGGGAGGGAGGAGGCCCCUCCCAAUCAGUGCAGGCUGAGGAGGUCAGGGGAUGGAGACUGCCCGGCCUGAUGGCCUGUCCAGGCCCUUGGAGGGUCAAGUCUGGAGUUCUCUCAUCUCUGUUUUUGUUUUUGUCCCUUGCUGUCAUGCGCACUACAGCGACGCCUUGACAUGCCCCUAUUUUUCUCUUCCUACCUCUUUCCUACGUUUCCAUUAUUCUCUGUCUUCCCACUGAUUUGGAAUCCAGUCUCAUUCCCACUGGAGUUGCAUAUACUAGCUGUGUGCUUGCACCUUGCAGCCAUGAAGAAGACACUCGGGAUGUUAAACCUGAGCAUGAUAACCAUGUCCUCCUCCCAAGGCUCUGGGACAUCAAUUAGAGAGUCCGGGACGGGGGUCUCUCUGACUGGCAUCUGGCUUGGAUGCUAUCUGUGGUUCUCUAGGAUUACCAUGCAAACUCUUAAGAUACAGCCUCAGGUGCCACACACUCAGUUCCCAGGCCUUCCCCCACCUUAUGAGGAGAGGAAAAAUAAGAUCGCCUAAGGCCCACUCACCUUCCUCCCUCAACAUCUGCCUGUUGGUUUUGGAGGAGGGUCAGAGUAUGCUAGGAUUUGUCUAAAUCAUUUAUAGCCUUUUGAAUAUAGAACGAAAGGAAACAGAUGGCAGUGACAUGAUUACACUGUGAGACAUUGAUGCUAACUCCUGCCACUUUCCCUUCCCAAGUUCUGGGAAUUCCCUGGGUGGAGGGGGUAAGAUAAUUAAUGGUAAUUAAGACUUAGUAUGUAUGGAUUACUAUACUAGGAGCUUUACGUGCAUUACUUUACUAGAUCCUCUUUCCAGCUAUUCAUUCAUUCAUCCACUUGACAAAUGCUUACUGCUCUUCUACUAUGUGUCAGGCACUGUUCUACACCCUGGGAUUAACGAUGAAUGCAACAGAUGUGUCCUUUCUCUCCGGGAGAUUGCAGCCUAGGGGGAGGAAGACAUUAACCAGAUAACCCCACAUGUAAAUGUAAAUGUGCUACUGUGAGAAGCUUAAGAAGGGGAGAUUUGUGGCUCUAGGAGAGCUCAUUAACAGAAAGUUUGACUGAUAUCAGAAAAGGCUUCCUUGAAGAAGUUACACUACAGCUGAAAUGUGAAGAAUGAGUAUAAGUUAAGUAGGUGAGGAGGAGAAAGUUUUCCAAGAACAGACAACAGAGUGUGCAAAGAAUCUGUGGCAAGAGGGGCAUGGUAAGUACAAAGAUGGGAAAAGGCCAUGAUGGCUGGAGUUGGGAGAGUAAAAGAGCAGUGGAAAACCACUGAGCAUUUACAACCAGGUAGCGGUGGUGACCAUGGGAGGGAUUAAUCAGAAUUGCAGUAUGGAGAAUGCAUUGGGAGGGGUAGAGUGGAUUCUGGUUAAGUUAGGAGAUUGUUAUCUUCAUUCUGAUGAGAGACGGAUAAUAGGGGCUAGAGUGGAGUGUUGGUAGUGGAGAUAGGAAAGGAAUGGGUCAAGCCAUAUUUAGAAGGUAAAAAUCCACCCGACUUGGUGCUGGAUUAGUCAUGGGGAGGAUCACGAUGAGGAAGAGGGGUAUUAAAGCUAACUUGAUGUCUGGCUUGCCCAAAGGAAUGGAGGAUCCACUAAAAUGUCCACUCCAUGAGAGUGUCUGUUUUGGUCACAGCUCUGUCUCCUGUGCCUGGCACAGAGUUGGUGUUCAAUAAAUAUUUAUUGAAUGGCAGUGUUGACAAUUAAUGGAGAGACUAUGAAAAGAGGCCUAGACUUGGAGAGGAAGAUCAUGAGUUCAGCUUUGUACCUGUUGAGUUUCAGAUGCCUUUAAACAACCAAGAAGAGUUGUCAUGGACAUCAGAGUAAAGCUCUGAUGUGAAUUACCUCAUUGAAGAAGCUGCCAAAAUGAAGAAGAUCAAGUUUCAGCACAUCGUGUCUAUCUACGGGGUGUGCAAGCAGCCCCUGGGUAUUGUGAUGGAGUUUAUGGCCAACGGCUCCCUGGAGAAGGUGCUGUCCACCCACAGCCUCUGCUGGAAGCUCAGGUUCCGCAUCAUCCAUGAGACCAGCUUGGCCAUGAACUUCCUGCACAGCAUUAAGCCGCCUCUGCUCCACCUGGACCUCAAGCCGGGCAACAUACUCCUGGACAGCAACAUGCAUGUCAAAAUUUCAGACUUCGGCCUGUCCAAGUGGAUGGAACAGUCCACCCGGAUGCAGUACAUCGAGAGGUCGGCUCUGCGGGGCAUGCUCAGCUACAUCCCCCCUGAGAUGUUCCUGGAGAGUAACAAGGCCCCAGGACCUAAAUAUGAUGUGUACAGCUUUGCAAUUGUCAUCUGGGAGCUACUCACUCAGAAGAAACCAUACUCAGAGCUCACGUCACAGCUAAAGGAAAGGAAAGGGUUCAACAUGAUGAUGAUUAUUAUCCGAGUGGCGGCAGGCAUGCGGCCCUCCCUACAGCCUGUCUCUGACCAAUGGCCAAGCGAGGCCCAGCAGAUGGUGGACCUGAUGAAACGCUGCUGGGACCAGGACCCCAAGAAGAGGCCAUGCUUUCUAGACAUUACCAUCGAGACAGACAUACUGCUGUCACUGCUGCAGAGUCGUGUGGCAGUCCCAGAGAGCAAGGCCCUGGCCAGGAAGGUGUCCUGCAAGCUGUCGCUGCGCCAGCCCGGGGAGGUUAAUGAGGACAUCAGCCAGGAACUGAUGGACAGUGCAGACUCAGGAAACUACCUGAAGCGGGCCCUUCAGCUCUCCGACCGUAAGAAUUUGGUCCCGAGAGAUGAGGAACUGUGUAUCUAUGAGAACAAGGUCACCCCCCUCCACUUCCUGGUGGCCCAGGGCAGUGUGGAGCAGGUGAGGUUGCUGCUGGCCCACGAGGUAGACGUGGACUGCCAGACGGCCUCUGGAUACACGCCCCUCCUGAUCGCCGCCCAGGACCAGCAACCCGACCUCUGUGCCCUGCUUUUGGCACAUGGUGCUGAUGCCAACCGAGUGGAUGAGGAUGGCUGGGCCCCACUGCACUUUGCAGCCCAGAAUGGGGAUGACGGCACUGCGCGCCUGCUCCUGGACCACGGGGCCUGUGUGGAUGCCCAGGAACGUGAAGGGUGGACCCCUCUUCACCUGGCUGCACAGAAUAACUUUGAGAAUGUGGCACGGCUUCUGGUCUCCCGUCAGGCUGACCCCAACCUGCAUGAGGCUGAGGGCAAGACCCCCCUCCAUGUGGCCGCCUACUUUGGCCAUGUUAGCCUGGUCAAGCUGCUGACCAGCCAGGGGGCUGAGUUGGAUGCUCAGCAGAGAAACCUGAGAACACCACUGCACCUGGCAGUAGAGCGGGGCAAAGUGAGGGCCAUCCAACACCUGCUGAAGAGUGGAGCGGUCCCUGAUGCCCUUGACCAGAGCGGCUACGGCCCACUGCACACUGCAGCUGCCAGGGGCAAAUACCUGAUCUGCAAGAUGCUGCUCAGGUACGGAGCCAGCCUUGAGCUGCCCACCCACCAGGGCUGGACACCCCUGCAUCUAGCAGCCUACAAGGGCCACCUGGAGAUCAUCCAUCUGCUGGCAGAGAGCCACGCAAACAUGGGUGCUCUUGGAGCUGUGAACUGGACUCCCCUGCACCUAGCUGCACGCCACGGGGAGGAGGCGGUGGUGUCAGCACUGCUGCAGUGUGGGGCUGACCCCAAUGCUGCAGAGCAGUCAGGCUGGACACCCCUCCACCUGGCGGUCCAGAGGAGCACCUUCCUGAGUGUCAUCAACCUCCUAGAACAUCACGCAAAUGUCCACGCCCGCAACAAGGUGGGCUGGACACCCGCCCACCUGGCCGCCCUCAAGGGCAACACAGCCAUCCUCAAAGUGCUGGUCGAGGCAGGCGCCCAGCUGGACGUCCAGGAUGGAGUGAGCUGCACACCCCUGCAACUGGCCCUCCGCAGCCGAAAGCAGGGCAUCAUGUCCUUCCUAGAGGGCAAGGAGCCGUCAGUGGCCACUCUGGGUGGUUCUAAGCCAGGAGCCGAGAUGGAAAUUUAGACAACUUGGCCAGCCGUGGUGGCUCACGUCUGUAAUCCCAGCACUUUGGGAGGCUGAGGCAGGCAGAUCACCUGAUAUCAA